UUUUUUUUUUUUGAGACGAAGUCUCACUCUGUCACCCAGGCUGGAGUGCAGCAGCAUGAUCUUGGCUCACUGCAACCUCUGCCUCCCGGGUUCAAGCAAUUCUCUGCCUCAGCCUCCCAAGUAGCUGGGAUUACAGGCGCCUGCCACCACGCCUGGCUAGUUUUUGUAUUUUUAGUAGAGAUGGGGUUUCACCAUCUUGGCCAGGCUGGUCUUGAACUCCUGACCUUGCGUUCUACCCGCCUUGGCUUCCCAAAGUGCUGGGUCUGUCACCCAGGCUGGAGUGCAAUGGUGCAAUCAUGGCUCACUGCAGCGUCAACCUCCCUGGGCUCAGAUGAUUCUCCCACCUUAGCCUCUCAAGUAGCUGGGAUUAAAGGCAUAUGCCACCAUGCCCAGCUAAUUUUUCUAUUUUUUUUGUAGAGACAGGGCAUCCCUACCUUGCCCAGGCUGGUCUUGAACUCCUGGUUUCAAAGGAUCCUCCUGCUUCAGCCUCCCAAAGCACUGGGUCUAUUAUUCCCUUUCAUAUUCAAACUUAAUUCUGCAUUUUCAAGGCCUUGAAUUUUCAAGGGCAGCUUUUUCUGUCCCUGAACUUAAUCUUCAGCUCCUCUCACCUCCUGGGAGGUUGGGGGGUGGGGAAGAAAAGUCCCAACCCUCUAAUCCUGCUUUGGUCUUUUGCUGCCAGCCCCCAUCCUGAAGCUACCAGUCAAUUUGUUUGCAUACAAGAAGAUAUCACUUUGGAGAUUCUAAGUGUAUACGAGGAAAUGAGGUCAAAGACCAAAUAUAUAUAUUUCACUAUAUCACACUUCAAACUUUUGUUUACUGUUUCCCUUCUCCUACUCUAUUAUAAACCUUUGAGGGUGGGGACUGUGAGUUAUUUAUCUUUAUAUUCCCAGUGUCAAGAGUGUUUAGCUAUAAUGGGAAUGAAUCUCAAAGUUUCUUGAAUAAAUGACAAGAAGAAUCAUAGUUGCAUGAACUAAAUUCAUUAUUCUCAGUCCUUGAGGUAAAUGAAUAUAUUGAUAUUAUGUCUGCUUACUCUUUUUUUGCGAGAGAGAGAAAGAGGAGGGAGGGAGGGAAGGAAGGAAAAAAGGAAGGAAGGCGAAAAGAGAGAAAGACAGAAAAGAGAGAGAAAAAGAGAGAGAAAGAAGGAAGGGGAGGGAAGGAAGGAAAAGAAGGAGGGAAGAAGGGAAAGGGAGGGAGAGGAAGAAAAGAAAGAAGAAGGAAGGAAAGAAAGAAAGAAGAAAAGGAGGGAGGAAGGAACGAAGAAAGGGAAAGAAGGAGGGAGGGAGGGAAAUGAAGGAAAGAAAGAAAAAAGAAAGAAAGAAAAAAGAAAGAAGAAAAGGAGGGAGGAAGGAAGGAGGGAGGGAAGGAUGGAAGAAAGGGAAAGAAGGAGGGAGGAAGGGACAUGAAGAGAAUAAAGAAAGAAAGAAGAAAAGAAAAGAAAAAAGAAAAGAAAAGGGAGGGCUCUGCGGGUGGCGGCGGCGCGGGGAGCCGGUUGCAGGCCGAGAUGCUGCAGAUGGACCUGAUCGACGCGACGGGGGACACUCCCGGGGCCGAGGACGACGAGGAGGACGACGACGAGGAGCGCGCGGCCCGGCGGCCGGGAGCGGGGCCGCCCAAGGCCGAGUCCGGCCAGGAGCCGGCGUCCCGCGGCCAGGGCCAGAGCCAAGGCCAGAGCCAGGGCCCGGGCAGCGGGGACACGUACCGGCCCAAGCGGCCCACCACGCUCAACCUCUUUCCGCAGGUGCAGUUGUCUCAGGACACACUGAAUAAUAAUUCUCUGGGCAAAAAGUACAGUUGGCAGGAUCGGGUGUCUCGAUCAUCCUCACCCCUGAAGACAGGGGAGCAGACACCACCGCAUGAACCCAUUUGCCUGAGCGAUGAGCUGCCCCCCCAGAGCAGCCCCGCCCCCACCACAGAUCGAGGCACCUCCACCAACAGCCCACGCUGCUGGUAG